GCGUCUGCCGCAGCAACGGGGUGCGGCAGGGUGGGGAACGCGGGAGCGGGGCCAGCUCCCAGGAAAGCUGGUCUGCGAGCGGCCCCUGCCCGGCUCCCAGGUCCCUGCGCGACCCCGCCCUUCCCGAGACCCCAGCCGGGCUGCCGCCCGCGUCCCGGAAGCUCCAGCCUGAACCAUGUUUUUCACUUGUGGCCCAAAUGAGGCCAUGGUGGUCUCCGGGUUCUGCCGAAGCCCCCCAGUCAUGGUGGCUGGAGGGCGUGUCUUUGUCCUGCCCUGCAUCCAACAGAUCCAGAGGAUCUCUCUCAACACACUGACCCUCAAUGUCAAGAGUGAAAAGGUUUACACUCGCCAUGGGGUCCCCAUCUCAGUCACUGGCAUUGCCCAGGUAAAAAUCCAGGGGCAGAACAAGGAGAUGUUGGCGGCCGCCUGUCAGAUGUUCCUGGGGAAGACGGAGGCUGAGAUUGCCCACAUUGCCCUGGAGACGUUAGAGGGCCACCAGAGGGCCAUCAUGGCCCACAUGACUGUGGAGGAGAUCUAUAAGGACAGGCAGAAAUUCUCAGAACAGGUUUUCAAAGUGGCCUCCUCAGACCUGGUCAACAUGGGCAUCAGUGUGGUUAGCUACACUCUGAAGGACAUUCACGAUGACCAGGACUAUUUGCACUCUUUGGGGAAGGCUCGAACAGCUCAAGUCCAAAAAGAUGCACGGAUUGGAGAAGCAGAGGCCAAGAGAGAUGCUGGGAUCCGGGAAGCUAAAGCCAAGCAGGAAAAGGUGUCUGCUCAGUACCUGAGUGAGAUCGAGAUGGCCAAGGCACAGAGAGAUUACGAACUGAAGAAGGCCGCCUAUGACAUCGAGGUCAACACCCGCCGAGCACAGGCUGACCUGGCCUAUCAGCUUCAGGUGGCCAAGACUAAGCAGCAGAUUGAGGAGCAGCGGGUGCAGGUGCAGGUGGUGGAGCGGGCCCAGCAGGUGGCAGUGCAGGAGCAGGAGAUCGCCCGGCGGGAGAAGGAGCUGGAGGCCCGGGUGCGGAAGCCAGCGGAAGCGGAGCGCUACAAGCUGGAGCGCCUAGCCGAGGCAGAGAAGUCCCAACUAAUUAUGCAGGCGGAGGCAGAAGCCGCGUCUGUGCGGAUGCGUGGGGAAGCUGAGGCCUUUGCCAUAGGGGCCCGAGCCCGAGCCGAGGCUGAGCAGAUGGCCAAGAAGGCAGAAGCCUUCCAGCUGUACCAAGAGGCUGCUCAGCUGGACAUGCUGCUAGAGAAGCUGCCCCAGGUGGCAGAGGAGAUCAGUGGUCCCUUGACUUCAGCCAAUAAGAUCACACUGGUGUCCAGCGGCAGUGGGACCAUGGGGGCAGCCAAAGUGACUGGGGAAGUACUGGACAUUCUAACUCGCCUGCCAGAGAGUGUGGAAAGACUCACAGGCGUGAGCAUCUCCCAGGUGAAUCACAAGCCUUUGAGAACAGCCUGAGCCUUCAGCCCUCACAGAUGCCCAGCCUCAUAGCUGAAGUUGCCUGAAUGAUCCUCCUGUUGCAUGUAACCCACUGGCCUCCCUGAGCAUGUCCAUUGACAGUGAGGUCCCACCCCUCAUCUCUCCUUGCCAAAUAGUUUGUGCCUUGUCUUGAAGGGGGUUGCUCCCCUUGCCAACCUCACACUGCUAUGAUUGCCAACUCCAGCGGUCCCAUGUCAGCCUUCUGAUGAUCCCACUCCACCCCACCUCAACUUAUUUAACUUCCUAAUUAAAUCAGACUGUUUGAGCCUGUUGUCUAGAAUAUUUUCCUGACCAAGACUGAGGGAUGGGCUGGAGGUUUUCAACUUUGCUACCCAAAUAAAUUGCUGUAAGUAAGUACUAAUAAAACAGAAGCAACUGGAAAUUAA